AUGUUCUCUAUUUUAAAAGGUAAGAAUGAGAUCACUUAGCUAAUUCACCAAUCAAGAGUAGUUCAGUGGAUUACUUUCAUCCUUAUACUAUUAUCAAGUUGAGCAGGGCUGAUCCUUAUCAACUUUUCUGGCUUCAAAGCUAGGAAUCAGUGUAAAAGGGCUAAAAAAUCUUUUACUCAACAGAUGGGAUCCACUUAAGUGGUCUGUCCAUACUUUUAACCCACUGUUCUUUUGAAGUGAACACCAUCAUACAGUGGGCAAACUUCUGCUUAUUCAACACUUUAAAAAUACCUUUAAAAUGAGAAAUCUCCAAAAAACAAGCCGUGGUUUCUUAUAAGUGUUUUUCACAGAUGUACUAAAGUAAGCGUUUCCUUUCACACUCUUUGCGCCUAACCGUCUACAUGAUAGGGCCAAACCCAGGUUAAAUAUUUUUUUCCAGCUACCACUCUGGACACACCAACUAAUUAUGCACACCUCACAAAACCACCUUUCAAAAUGCAGAGAGAAUUAACAGCAAGGAAGUAAAGAUUUUUCUAAAUAUAGUCCCAUCAUAUUUAUUUCACACUCAUCAAGUAGGUCACUGGAGGUAGCUGGCAGCUAGGGACACUCAGAUGCAUCUCUCAAAGCCAAGGCUGAGACCAAGGGGUCACUGACAGCUGCGCCAUCUACCUGUUGCAGCUGGGCCACUGCUCUGGACAACUGUCAGAUCAGCUUCUUCGUCCUACAAAUACUAAUGACUGGAUUUUUAAAAUCGUUGUUUGCCACCCUUUCUUCCCGCCCCCCAACCCCAUCGGGCCGCUCGGGCAGGGCCAAGGGCGCCGCGGGACUCACGAGCUCCCCUCCGCGCUGGCUGCAGCGGCGAUGCCGGGCAUGCCUGGCCGGGCCCGGCCGGGGGCGGCCUCGCUGCCGGGGCAGGGACCUCGCAGGCCGGCGCGCAGAGGCGAGGAACCCUCCCGGCGCCAUCGACUCACCUACCCGCGGAGAGGCGACGGCGCGCGCCGCUCACCAGCCCGGGCCCCAGAUCCAAGGAGGAGGGGCAGCGGCGCGGGGACCCUGUGGUGGGUGUCGUAAGGAGGAAAACGUGUUACCUAAGCCGGGGAUGAGGACAGAGCAGGAGGCAGCAGCCUUUCCCUCGAGAAACGGAAGCGGCGGGGAGCAGGAGGAGGAGGAGGCGCGGCCCGGGCGCGAGGUUAGGCGAGGGGCGCUGGGCGUGCGGCCGCAGGCGCGGCCAGAGGACGAGGGUUGGGGAGGACGGCGGAGGUCACGCGAGCGAAGGCGAAGCCCCGGCGACGCACGGCCCCGCUUGGCUCGGCACCGGAUCCGAGCUUGGCCUCAGCCAGGCCGCCGCCCCCGGCUUUCCCGCGGGACCGCGGCGUGGAAACGCGCGCUGCCGCCUCGGGGCUCCCGGGACGCGCGGGCCCCCCACGCCUGCCCGAGCCGGGCGUCCGCGACGUCACAAGUGGAGCGCGAUGAUUCAGAGGGAGGGCCAGGAAGGGAAGGGCUCUGGGGUCAGCUUGGCCACGGCUGCUGUUUCCUUGUCGCCGCCCACGAAUUCACUUUUAAAUCUUCCUCCUCCAUUCAUCUGUACUCUCAUAGGGGACUGCGGGUUUGACAGAUGGGUUGGCAGCUGUGAAGAUGGACUUCCUGCCAGUGGUAUCCGGGUCCCACUGUUCUAAUGGAAAUGUCAGGUGUACUGGAUGUUCCUCAAGACACAGCAGUGUCUCUGGGCCUUGCCUCUUAAGGAGUGGGCCUCGGGCCACCUGGACAGGAAGCGCAUCAAGGGUGGGGAACUUAUCUCUCUCCAGCCUUUGGUGCUGUGAUACUCAGUGUACCUUAAGGAUGGUUUGGGUUGAACCUAGGUAGGAAUGGGUGUUGGUGGGCGGGGUGGGGGUGGGGGGAAUAGAAACCUUAAAAGGGCAACACAAAGUUUUGAAUAGAAGAGGCCAAGCAGCCUCGCCCAGAAGCUGAUGUUUGUGAAUGUACUGGGCCUUCUAAAGCGGCGCUUCACACACCUUUUCACUUCUUGGCACAGGUAGGAAAGGAUGAUAUUACAAGGGUCAAAAUGGGGGUAAACAGAAGAGGCUGCUCCUGCAGAAGGCUUCCUGCAGAAGCCCUUGCACUUGGAGGGCUGGGAAGACCCAUGCUGUAUCUGCAUCCCUGUCAUUCGUUUCACGGCAUCCAGUUGGGAAGCUCUGCUUAAAGCUUUGUCUGGCACGUUUUCUUAGCUACAUUUUUCCACUCCAGCUGAGACUGCCUCACUGAGUUGUCAACACUUGGUCUUCUUCAGCAGUGAGGAACCAACAAGACAGGAGGCUGGGUCAAUACUCAACUUGGCAAACUCCAGGAAAUGGUGCUUAAAACGUUUGGCUUCUUGAAUGGAAUUCAUGGUACUGCUCCCAGCCUGCACCUGGGUUCUCCAACUUGAGACAAUUUCUCCCCGCAUCCCCCCACCCUUCCCUGGCUUUCACUCACUAGCAAGUGGGCUGCUUCUACUUUCUUUCUCACAUUCAUUUCUUAGGUCCAUUCUCAGAGCGGUUAGGAUUACUGUUUAAUUAGCCUCAUAAUCAUAUCUAUGAUGGCAAAAUCAAGAAACAAUUUAAACAUGAUUCUUAAAAGUAAGGAGAUAAAUACCAGAGACAUAGAAGGUGAAAGAAUUUGCCUCUAGGAAGCAGGAAUUUAAAUUUGGGGAAGACAGGGUGGAGCAAGGGAUAUAAAUCUAGUCCAUUUUUCUUUUCUUUUCUUUUCUUUUUUUUUUAUUUUUAAGAUAGAGUCUCACUCUGUCGCCCAGGCUGGAGUGCAGUGGCAUGAUCUUGGCUCACUGCAACCUCUGCCUCCUUCGUUCAAGCGAUUCUCCCACCUCAGCCUCCCUAGUAACUGGGAUUACAAGUGACUGCCACUAUGCCCAGCUAAUUUUGUAUUUUUAGUAGAGACGAGGUUUCACCAUGUUGGCCAGGCUGGUCUCGAACUCCUGACCUCAGGGGAUCCGCCCAGCUCAGCCUCCCAAAGUGCUAGGAUUCCAGGCGUGAGCCACUGCACCUGGCGGAAUCUAGUCCAUUUUCCACUUUGCUACCACACAUCUGCAGGGUUUCUUGCUUGCUUAAAAGCUUUCAUUGGCUCCCAAUCUCUGAUAAUAUCAAGAGCAAGUUCCUGAACAACUCAUUCAAGACCCAUCACCCCUCGCAUCUGUCAACUCUGCCCCUUGAAUAUUACACCUCAUUUUACUACACCACAUCUAGUUCCCUGAAUAUGCAAACAGAUUUCAUACAUUUGCACCUUUAUACAUGUUAUUGCUUUUGCCUGGGAGAGUAUUCUCUUGCUGCUAUAAUAAUAGCUAAUGACACUGUGCUAAGUACUUUCUGUGAUUUAUAACUGUUAAUUCUUACAUCAACCCUAUGGUAAAUGUUACUGUUAUCUCCAUUUUAUAAACAAGAAAACUAAGACUUAAAGAGUUUAAGUGAUUUGCAGAAAUAUGUAGUAUUUGGUGAGGCUAAAUUUGAACCCAGCAAUCUGACUCCAGGACUAACAUAAUAUUACCUAUUCAUCCUUCUAAAAUGUUUCCCAGACACUAAAUUUGAACAGGAUUAAAAGAUUUAAAUGUUUUUAAGUCUUAAAAGGGCAAGGAGAAAAUACAAGUGAAUUGCUUUUAAUCUCAAACUAAGCAUGAAACAACGGCUGAAAUUACAAAGGAAAAGUGACAGAUCUGACUGUUGAACUUUUAACUUCUUUUAUCCAAAAAAAAACCCCAUAGAAUAAAAUUUAAAAACAAGUAAAAAUUACAAAAAAUUUGCAAUAUACAUGACAGAUAAGCAUAACAUUAAAGAGAACUUAGAAAGAAAAAAUAGCCUACUAAAAAUGAGCAAAAUGCAAAUUCGUCAUCAUGAGAGAAAAAUGUAAAUGGCCAAACAUUUUUAAGAGAAGUAAAAACUUAAAACGAUAAUGCACCAUCAAAUUGAGAAUAAAAUAAUACUCAGAGCUAGUAAUUUGGGCCAGUGACCCUUGGAGUAGGAUGUAUAGCAACUAAAGAAACUCAUACAUUACUGAGAAGGGUGUAAAUUGGCUCAACGAUUCUGGAGAGCAAUUUGACAGAAUGUAGUGAAAGCGUCAAAAAUGUUCACACACUUUGACUUAAAAAUUACAUUCCUGGAAAUUUAUAAUACAAACAUUUUCUAUAAAAGGUCAGAUGGCAAAUACUUUGGGCUUUGAAGGCCACAUAUGUCUCUGUGGCUUUUCUUUUGUGUGUGUGUUUAAAAAAAAAAAAAACUGCCCCCCCUCCCCCCACCCUUGUUAGGCCAUUCUUGCAUUACUAUAAAGAAAUACCUGAGGCUGGUUAAUUUAUAUGAAAAGAGGUUUAACUGGCUCAUGGUUCUGCAGGCUGUACAGGAAGCAUAAUGCCAUCUGCUUCUGGGGGGGCCUCAGGAAGCUUCCAAUCAUGCUGGAAGGUGAUGGGGAGCAGAUGUCUCACAUGGUGAGAACGGGAGCAAGAAGGAGUUGGGGGGGAGGAGCCACAUAAACAAUGAGAUCCCUGUGAGCUCAGAGUGAGAGCACACUUAUCACCAAGGAGAUGGCCCAAGCUAUUCAUGAGGGAUCCGCCCCUAUGAUCCAAACACCUCCCACCAGGCUCCACCUCCAACACUGGAGAUUAUAUCUCAACAUGAAAUUUGAAUGGGACAUCCAAACUGUAUCACCCCCAAAAUGUAAAGUCUCAUCACAGUACAUUUGGUAAUGGCCAAAAGAGAAACCAAACUAAAUGUCCGAGAAUAAAAAUUAGUUACAACUAGAUACACGGAGGCAAGUUUUUAAAAAGUGUUAAAAUUUUAAAAUGUUGCAGAAUGGUAUCUAUUGGAUAAAAUAGUAUUUAUGAUUUAUUAAGUGGAAAAUACAGUUUACAAAAUAAUAUGGUGUGAUCCCGAAAACAACAUAAUCAUGUGUGUAUAAAUGCAUAGAAAAAAAUCUGGAAAGAUAUAAACAGAUAUUUAUAGUGGUCUAGGGCAGGGGAUGGAAUUGUAGAUAUUUGCUUUUUGUUUUAUGUAUAUGUUUCCCAUAAUGAAAUGUAUUGUUUAUAUAAUUAAAAAAUAUACGAAACUUUGCUUGGGGGACAACAAAGCACCUCAUUUGUUAAUUUGGGAAAAUCUUUUAUUACAAUCUCUGUAAGGAGUUGGUUGCUCUCUCUUCUGUACUCCCUGAUUACAUAAUGCUCUUCUGAGCACUUUUAUUUAAUAGCAGAAUGGUUGAUAUCAUUAUUUAGUUAAGGUUUCCUCUAUUAUCGAACAUCUGAGUUCCCAGUACACUAGUCUCCCCUUAUCUGUGGUUUUGCUUCCAAGGUUUCAGUUAUGAUCAACCAAGAUCUGAAAAUAUUAAAUGAAAAAUUCCAGAAAUAAAACAAUUCAUAAGUUUUACAUUGUGCACCAUCCUGCUGUAUCCUGUCCAGGCCAUGGGUCAUCCCUCUUGUUCAGUGUGUCCACACUGUAGAUGCUCCCCUGUCUGUUAGUCACUUUGUAGUUGGCUUGGUUGUCAGACCUACUGUCAAGGUAUUGCAGUACUUAUGUCCAAGUAACACUUAUUUAACUUAAUAAUGGCCCCUAAACACAAGAGUAGUAAUGUUGGCAAUUUGGGUAUGCCAAAGAAAAGUCAUAAAGUGCUUCUUUUAAGUGAAAACCCAAAAGUUUUUGAAUUAGUAAGGAAAGAAAAAAAUCCAUAUGCUGAGGUCGCUAAGAUCUAUGAUAAGAAUGAAUCUUCUACCUGUGAAAUUGUGAAGGAAAAAGAAAUUCACGUUAGUUUUGCUGUUGUACCUCAAACUGCAAAAGUUAUGGCCACAGUGUAUAACUUUUAUUAAAAUAUAUUUGUAUAACUGUUCUUAUUUUACUUUUCUGUUUUAUUUUUAGAGACAGGGCUUCAUUCUGUCACCCAGGCUGGAGUGCAAAGGUGCAAUCAUAGCUCACUGCAGCCUCAAACUCUUUGGCUCAAGUGAUCUUCCUGCCUCAGCCUCCCAAGUAGCUGGGACUGCAGGUGUGCAUCACUACGCCCAGCUAAUUUUUUAAUUUUUUGUGCAGAUGGAGUCUGACUCUGUUGCCCAGGAACUCCUGGCCUCAAGUAAUCCUCCCGCCUCGGUUUUCCAAAGAGCUGGGAUUACAGGCAUGAGCCACUGUGCCUGGCUAUUCUAUUUUAUUAGCAGUAAUUGUUGUUAAUCUCUUAUUGUGCCUUAUUUAUAUUAAUAACUUAAUCAUAGAUAGAUAUGUAUAGGAAAAAACAUUGUAUAUAAAGGGUUCAGUACUAUCUGCAGUUUCAGAUAUCCAUGAGGGGUCUUGAAACGUAUCCCCCACAGGUAAGGGGGGACUUGUAUUUCUCUGUUAUAAAUAUGCUGGUUAUUCUCCACUUGUUGUGUUUUAGUGCCAUCUUCUGCUCUUCUCUGCUAGACUCUGUGCCUCAGAAGGUGGAAUUUUUCAUAAACUAUUCCAGCUGGGGUCUCAUGCCAGUUGGUUUUGACCAAUGGGUAACACCAUCAGUAGAUUGGAGGAUGGAAAAGGAAAAAAGGUUAGGAUAUGUUUCACCACCUCUUUUCCUGCUUCUGGCUGGGUUCUGAUGGUGGCUUUGUCCCUUGAAGGCUCCUCCUGCAAGGCAGCCCUGCUCCACUGUGCCAGCCUUCACUGGGCUCUACUAACGUGAUUCCCUCCCCUUAUUUCUUCAGGCCUAGCUGUGCUAACUCCUAGGUACCUCCAUGUUUCUUGUUUCCUUUCAUCCAACCCUAACCCUAACUUCUAUAAAUAGUUCCCGCAAUAAAGUCUCUUCAGCUGAAA